AAACCCGGAGGGCGGCGCGCGCGAACCGUGUCCGAACCGCACGGCGGCGUCCUGGGGGGUCCACUGUGAGGACGGGGGGUCCACUGUGAGGACGGAGCUUCCUCUCCUCAGGACCCACCCAGGAGGGGCCGGGGCUUGGGACACCUGGGGACACCUGGGGCCGCGUCCGCUGUGAGGACAGGGAGACGCUGCUGCAGCUCCGGGACACCUGGGGCCACCGAGGCGAAGGGGUAAAUCUUUUCAAGACACUAAAACAGGUGACUCAGCCCUGUGAGCUCUGUGCCUGACAUGACCCAAACGGCCAGCAAUUUUCUCCUUCUCCAGUUAAACCUGUCCAAAAUUGAGGAACCUAUCCAGGUGAGAACUGGCAACUCUAAUGUACUCCGAUACCUUUCUGCAGGAGAUUCAAAUAUUUGCUAAUGCUUACUGAUACCUUCACUGGUUAGAUCGAGGCAUUCCCCACCCCAUCUGAAAAAUGUUUACCAGAAGAAAUAACUCCUCAGUUUCGGUAAUCUAAAAGCCUGCAAAGUGACAAUGGCCCAUCUUUCACAGCAGGCGUAACCCAACACCUAUCCUCAGCUUUAAGAAUCCAAUAUUACCUUCACUCUGUGUGGAGACCGCAGUCCUCUGGAAAGGUGAAAGGGCUAAUCCUACUCUACAGAAGACUCCAGCUAAAUCAGACGCCUGACUAUCUCCAACACCCAUAGCUUACUGCGGGUUUGAACUGCUCCAAAGUAAAACGUAUAAUUAAGUCCUGUUGAGUUAACAUAUGGAAGGCCUUUCCUAACCACAGAUCUCCUAAUAGAUGAAAUGAAUCUCCAUUACAAAAAUAUCAAUCUAGGACAGGUGCAAAGGCACUCCGUGCAUAUGGAAACAAGCGUCUUCCCCUCCCACAUGGGAGGAAAAUUCAGUUUCAGCUCAGCUAGGGAUCUAGUCUUACUAAAGACGUGGGAAGAAGUUCUCCAGCUGAGCAGCUUUCCCCAACGUGGAAGGGACCAUAGCAAGGACACCUGAGUUCUCCAACAGACGUUCAACGCCAAGGGAUUCACAGUUCUGGGAGGUGAUCUCUGAUGAACAUGCCAUCGACUCCGCUGGCACCUACCACGGGGACAGCCACCUGCAGCUGGAGCGCAUCAACGUGCACCACCACGAGGCCAGCGGUGGCAGGUACGUGCCCCGCGCUGUGCUCGUGGAUCUGGAGCCGGGCACCAUGGACUCUGUGCACUCGGGGCCCUUCGGGCAGGUCUUCAGGCCAGACAACUUCAUUUCCGGGGAAGCUGCUGUCCUGUAACUCUGGAGGAGGGAGUUUCAUUUGCUCCACCUGCAGGGCGAAUGGUGCUUUCACCUCACAUGUGACACUUGGCCCUUUCUGCAUUAUGGUGGUGACCACUGAUGACCGUAUACCUGGCCGUCGAGUGACCGGCUGUGCUGUCUUACAGGUGUCGGACACCGUGGUGGAGCCCUACAACGCCACCCUCUCAGUCCACCAGCUCAUAGAAAACGCGGAUGAGACCUUCUGCAUAGAUAACGAAGCGCUAUAUGACAUAUGUUCCAGGACCCUAAAACUGCCCACACCCACCUAUGGUGACCUGAACCACCUGGUGUCUGCUACCAUGAGUGGGGUCACCACAUGCCUGCGCUUCCCAGGCCAGCUGAAUGCUGACCUGCGGAAGCUGGCCGUGAACAUGGUCCCGUUUCCCCGGCUGCAUUUCUUCAUGCCCGGCUUUGCCCCACUGACCAGCCGGGGCAGCCAGCAGUACCGGGCCUUGACUGUGGCUGAGCUCACCCAGCAGAUGUUUGAUGCUAAGAACAUGAUGGCUGCCUGUGACCCCCGUCACGGCUGCUACCUAACGGUGGCUGCCAUUUUCAGGGGUCGCAUGCCCAUGAGGGAGGUGGAUGAACAAAUGUUCAACAUUCAAGAUAAGAACAGCAGCUACUUUGCUGACUGGUUCCCCGACAACGUAAAAACAGCCGUCUGUGACAUCCCACCCCGGGGGCUAAAAAUGUCAGCCACCUUCAUUGGGAAUAAUGCGGCCAUCCAGGAACUCUUCACAUGUGUCUCAGAGCAGUUUACAGCAAUGUUCAGGCGCAAGGCCUUCCUCCACUGGUACACGGGCGAGGGCAUGGAUGAGAUGGAAUUCACCGAGGCCGAGAGCAACAUGAACGACCUGGUGUCUGAAUAUCAGCAAUAUCAGGAUGCCACGGCCGAGGAGGAGGAGGAUGAGGAGUAUGCCGAGGAGGAGGUGGCCUAGAACUCUCCUUUUCUAGGUAAAGGGGGGAAGCAGUGUGGAUUCUUUACUGUGUUCUGACAGCCAUGUGUCACUAUACGCUUGUUAAUUUGUGUCUUCACAUCUCCUGCUGCGUUUUAAAGCAUUUUUAUAGUAUGCGGUUUUGACUAAUAAAGUAUUCUCACAGCAU